CCUUCAGCCUCUGCUGUCUGGCCGCUCUGUCUAGGUCCUGGGCCACGGGAGAGCCCCGUCCCUCCUUUCUGAAGGCCCCCUGACUUGGGCCUCAGUGUCCCCGAAGAUCAUGAUGGCGUAUAUGAACCCGGGGCCCCACUAUUCUGUCAACGCCUUGGCCCUAAGUGGCCCCAGUGUGGAUCUGAUGCACCAGGCUGUGCCCUACCCAAGCGCCCCCAGGAAGCAGCGGCGGGAGCGCACCACCUUCACCCGGAGCCAACUGGAGGAGCUGGAGGCACUGUUUGCCAAGACCCAGUACCCAGACGUCUAUGCCCGUGAGGAGGUGGCUCUGAAGAUCAAUCUGCCUGAGUCCAGGGUUCAGGUUUGGUUCAAGAACCGGAGGGCUAAAUGCAGGCAGCAGCGACAGCAGCAGAAACAGCAGCAGCAGCCCCCAGGGGGCCAGGCCAAGGCCCGGCCUGCCAAGAGGAAGGCGGGCACGUCCCCAAGACCCUCCACAGAUGUGUGUCCAGACCCUCUGGGCAUCUCAGAUUCCUACAGUCCCCCUCUGCCCGGCCCCUCAGGCUCCCCAACCACGGCAGUGGCCACUGUGUCCAUCUGGAGCCCAGCCUCAGAGUCCCCUUUGCCUGAGGCGCAGCGGGCUGGGCUGGUGGCCUCAGGGCCGUCUCUGACCUCCGCCCCCUAUGCCAUGACCUACGCCCCGGCCUCCGCUUUCUGCUCUUCCCCCUCCGCCUAUGGGUCUCCGAGCUCCUAUUUCAGCGGCCUAGACCCCUACCUUUCUCCCAUGGUGCCCCAGCUAGGGGGCCCGGCUCUUAGCCCCCUCUCUGGCCCCUCCGUGGGACCUUCCCUGGCCCAGUCCCCCACCUCCCUAUCAGGCCAGAGCUAUGGCGCCUACAGCCCCGUGGAUAGCUUGGAAUUCAAGGACCCCACGGGCACCUGGAAAUUCACCUACAAUCCCAUGGACCCUCUGGACUACAAGGAUCAGAGUGCCUGGAAGUUUCAGAUCUUGUAGAGGACGCAGUCUCCAUCUCUCUCCAUCGGGCCUCGGGACCCUUUCUCUUCUGAAUCUGCUUCCCUGCAGUUUAGAUCCCGGGAUGGCAUUCCUGAGAAAGCAACCCGAACCAGCUGUCCUUCUGACAGCUCGGUGUUCAGCUUACAGAGACCACCCCUUUCCUCCACAGGGAGAGGCUCCUCCCUCUCCUGGGACAGCUCACAGGUCCUAGUGAUUCUCUCAACCCUAACACCGUCUGGCACGAUUGUGACCGCUGAAGUACACCACGAGCUCCAGGCUUCAGAAAGUGGUGCUGAGAACUUGCUCCAAGAAGAAGUCAAACCAAACUUGCAGUUGAUUUGGGGUCAUGUUUAGGUCAGAAUCACCGUGCCCUUGAACAAGCAGGUAGGGGGGCUUGAUAACUUAACUUUCCACGUGGACAGAAUUUUUUUUUUUGUUUUGUUUUUGUUUUGCAGACACAGUCUAGCUCUGUCGCCCAGGCUGGAGUGCAGUGGCACGAUCUCAGCUCACUGCAAGCUCUACCUCCCGGGUUCACGCCAUUCUCCUGCCUCAGCCUCCCGAGUAGCUGGGACUACAGAUGCCCACCACCAGGCCCGGCUAAUUUUUUUUGUAUUUUUAGUAGAGACGGGGUUUCACCGUGUUAGCCAGGAUGGUCUCGAUCUCCUGACCUCGUGAUCCGCCCGCCUCGGCCUCCCAAAGUGCUAGGAUUACAGGCGUGAGCCACCGCGCCCGGCCCUUUUUUUUUUUUUUUUUUUUAAUUGAGACGGAGUCUCACUCUUUUGCUUAGGCUGGAGUGCAGUGGUGUGAUCUCAGCUCACUGACUGCAACCUCCACCUCCCGGGUUGAAGCGUUGCUCCUGCCUCAAUCUCCCAAUUAGCUGGGAUUACAGGUGUGCUCCAUCAUGCCCGGCUAAUUUUUCUAUUAUUAGUAGAGACAGGGUUUUACCAUGUUGGCCAGGCUGGUCUGGAACCCCUGACCUCAAGUGAUCCGCCUGCCUCGGCCUCCCAAAGUGCUGGGAUUACAGGCAUGAGCCAUUGUGCCUGGCCCUACACGUGGACACUUCUUUAGCAUAUGGUUAGGGACCUUUCUAGAAAUUCCAAAGACAGACUUUAAGAAGCCCCGUCGGGAAACCUUAGGCCAAUGAUGUGGUUACAUUAAAAAUAAAUUAUCUGGGAAUUUCACAGACUUCACAAAUGUCAGGCUUACAUGGUAGGUUUAGGGGACCGUUUGAGAGACAAAGAUCUACAUUCAUAUAUGUAGCUAUACAUAUAUGUACUUUUUCUUCUUAGUUUCUUUUUAAAGACAUUUUAUCACUCAUUCGCUCAUUAGCACAUUGGGAAUGUGUGUAUUUGGUAGGGAAAUGAAAGGCACCUUGCCUGUUCCAUCUCUACUCCUUUUUUCUUUUGUUUUAGGAUUUUCUAAAGGUGAGACACUGGUGGAACUGGGGUAGCUGCUUGGGACGUACCACCUAUAGUUGUGGCUAUUUCACAGAGAAGCAGCAGCUAGACAGACUCCCAUCUGUAAAUAAACAAGAGAUAGGAAGAGGGGGAAAUAGAUUUGGAGGAGGCAGCCCUACAUUUCAAACAUACAUUCCCUUUUUUAGAUUUUUUUUUUUUUUUUUUUGGUUUUCAGUUUUGAUGGUGGGAUUGGAAAAUAGAGCUUGGCUUGAGGACAUUUUCCUGGGGUGGCACCAUUAUUUCUUGAAAUAGAAUCUUACUUAUGGUGACACUGGCAAGCACUUGUGAGAACCUGAAGACGGAUUGAGGUCAUUUGAUGCUCAGAAGUUGGGUGCUGGGUCCCUGCCUUCUCAGUCCGAGUUCUCCUUUCAUUUUUGGGUGGGGAGGCGGGUUCCAAGAGCCCUUCAUUGGUGGAGUUCACAAGGCAAGGUGUAAAAAAAAAAGUAGGGCAGGAAGACAGUGGUGUGCUGGCAGAGGUCUAACAAUGGGCUCUCCAAGGAAGAGGAAAAGGUUGGUUGUGGAGUGUUUGUCAGUUUCCGUGGUGUAAAUACUCCCACCACGGCUGACUUCAAGCUAGCAACCGGAGGUCACUGAACUAAGAGUUGGGAAGAGAUAGGGCACAAUAUAUGCUUACGAGUUGGUACACACCGUCAGCAGCAGCCAGGGUCAGGAGAAAGGCGAGAUGUGAAGAGAGGCCGGGAGGUAUCAGAUGACGUUUCCAGCACUAGACCAGAAGAGGUGCACACAGCCUAGACCCCCUGAGGGGUACACCCUGAUCUCUAGAGCCCACAAAGAGGUUUUUAUUCAACAUAAAACGUGUUCAUCUCUCAUAGGCCUGAGUCAUGCUGGGUUCUGGGACAUUAAGCCCAGGAGUGGGCCGGGUGCGGUGGCUCACGCCUGUAAUCCCAGCACUUUGGGAGGCCGAGGCGGGUGGAUCACCUGAGGUCAGGAGUUCGAGACCAGCCUGGCCAACAUGGUGAAACCCUGUCUCUACUAAUAAUACAAAAAUUAGCCGGGCAUGGUGGCACGCGCCUGUAAUCCCAGCUACUCGGGAGGCUGAGGCAGGAGAAUUGCUGGAACCCGGGAGGCGGAGGUUGAAGAGAGCAGAGAUUGUGCCACUGUGCUCUAGCCUGGGUCACAAGAGCGAAACUCCGUCUCAAUAAUAACAACAACAAAAAUAACCCAGGAGUGGCUCAAGAGUCCAGUGUGGGAUGAAAAUAUAAACAGAGGAAGACAACAUAUGUCACUGGGGAGGCUGGGGGAGCUAGACAAAAUUCACACGGGAGGGGCAGGGAUGAGACAAUAUUGUGCCCUGGGUCUGUGCAAACGUUGGGACCAGAAUCCACUAUAAGUUUCAUUCUUCGGAGACACGGAAGCUCUGCACUGGAGGCCGGGACUCAGGCGUGGAAGAGAAUCUUCUCCUUAUUCACCGGGGAGGCUGUGUCUUGUGCAAACAAGUCAUAGAAACUUGAUGGGAGUUGGGGAGGGACUGAAGGAUGCAUGCAAGGUUCUGGGAAGGAGUGAGAAGUAGUGAAGGCCAAGGGGCCCCCAUCACAGGCCGAUGGGGUAAGACUUCGAGAGAGCCUGAUCCUGGGGUCUUCUGAGACUCCACCAGGAGCCGGAGAGGGCAGGGAGCCAAAUCCAGCUAGGAGGUUACAGAUUGCUUUUCCUGGGCUGGGCUCCUGAGUGUUGGUUCUUCCAGCUGUGCACAGGGGAUUUCAAACGUUCUACGUCCUAAAGCCAGGAAGAGUGACAAGGCAGGUGGGGACAGAAGGAAGAAGCCAGGAGCCUCCCUGAGAAGGUGUCACCUUAUCUGUCCUCCUCUUCCCCACACACUGGCCUCUGGGUCCCCCUUCUCUGUCCACCCACAGAGUGAAACCAAUUAAAAUGUUGGAUCUCA